AUUUCCGUCCGCCGAGGAACCGACCGCCGCCGGCCGGGUUGCAGGCGGGGCACCUCGGGCAGGACCUCCCUGGUCGGAAGUGGCCGUGAGCCCAAGCCGCGGUCCCGGGCCGGCACCCAGGAUGGGCGAGGUGGAGGCCCCGGGCCGCUUGUGGCUCGAGAGCCCCCCUGGGGGAGCGCCCCCCAUCUUCCUGCCCUCGGACGGGCAAGCCCUGGUCCUGGGCAGGGGACCCCUGACCCAGGUUACGGACCGGAAGUGCUCCAGAACUCAAGUGGAGCUGGUCGCAGAUCCUGAGACCCGGACAGUGGCAGUGAAACAGCUGGGAGUUAACCCCUCAACUACCGGGACCCAGGAGUUGAAGCCGGGGUUGGAGGGCUCUCUGGGGGUGGGGGACACACUGUAUUUGGUCAAUGGCCUCCACCCACUGACCCUGCGCUGGGAAGAGACCCGCACACCAGAAUCCCAGCCAGAUACUCCGCCUGGCACCCCUCUGGUGUCCCAAGAUGAGAAGAGAGAUGCUGAGCUGCCGAAGAAGCGUAUGCGGAAGUCAAACCCCGGCUGGGAGAACUUGGAGAAGUUGCUAGUGUUCACCGCAGCUGGGGUGAAACCCCAGGGCAAGGUGGCUGGCUUUGAUCUGGACGGGACGCUCAUCACCACACGCUCUGGGAAGGUCUUUCCCACUGGCCCCAGUGACUGGAGGAUCUUGUACCCAGAGAUUCCCCGUAAGCUCCGAGAGCUGGAAGCCGAGGGCUACAAGCUGGUGAUCUUCACCAACCAGAUGAGCAUCGGGCGCGGGAAGCUGCCAGCCGAGGAGUUCAAGGCCAAGGUGGAGGCUGUGGUGGAGAAGCUGGGGGUCCCCUUCCAGGUGCUGGUGGCCACGCACGCAGGCUUGUACCGGAAGCCGGUGACGGGCAUGUGGGACCAUCUGCAGGAGCAGGCCAACGACGGCACGCCCAUAUCCAUCGGGGACAGCAUCUUUGUGGGAGACGCAGCCGGACGCCCGGCCAACUGGGCCCCGGGGCGGAAGAAGAAAGACUUCUCCUGCGCCGAUCGCCUGUUUGCCCUCAACCUUGGCCUGCCCUUCGCCACGCCUGAGGAGUUCUUUCUCAAGUGGCCAGCAGCCGGCUUCGAGCUCCCAGCCUUUGAUCCGAGGACUGUCUCCCGCUCAGGGCCUCUCUGCCUCCCCGAGUCCAGGGCCCUCCUGAGCGCCAGCCCGGAGGUGGUUGUCGCAGUGGGAUUCCCUGGGGCCGGGAAGUCCACCUUUCUCAAGAAGCACCUCGUGUCGGCCGGAUAUGUCCACGUGAACAGGGACACGCUAGGCUCCUGGCAGCGCUGUGUGACCACGUGUGAGACAGCCCUGAAGCAAGGGAAACGGGUCGCCAUCGACAACACAAACCCAGACGCCGCGAGCCGCGCCAGGUACGUCCAGUGUGCCCGAGCCGCGGGCGUCCCCUGCCGCUGCUUCCUCUUCACCGCCACUCUGGAGCAGGCGCGCCACAACAACCGGUUUCGAGAGAUGACGGACUCCUCUCAUAUCCCCGUGUCAGACAUGGUCAUGUAUGGCUACAGGAAGCAGUUCGAGGCCCCAACGCUGGCUGAAGGCUUCUCUGCCAUCCUGGAGAUCCCGUUCCGGCUAUGGGUGGAGCCGAGGCUGGGGCGGCUGUACUGCCAGUUCUCCGAGGGCUGAGCCCCGCCCAGCUCCCCUCCACAAUAAACGCUGUUUCUCCUUGA